CUCUCUCCCCAUCAUCCCCACAUCCCCGUAUCCCGCGCCGGCCGCUCGGGCUGAGGGCCGGGCUAUGCAGCUGUGGGGACCCGGGGGCUGCGGGCGCGCGUCCCUGCGGCGGCGUCCCCGGGGCCCGCGUCCCGUGCGCCCCCGCGCCCGCUGCGGGCGCCUGCUCCCUCCGCCGAGCGGCGUCUUUGUGUGCGGGGGUGUGGGAGGCGAGCGCGAGUCCGCGCAGCGCCGCCGAGUGCCCGCUCCCUCCCAGGGCGGGUGGGGGCCUCUCCGCGCCGCCCGCCGCCGCCGCCUCGCGAGGACGCCCGUCGCCCGCGCCGCCCGCACCGCGCCGGGCGCGCCGCCCCCGCCCGCCGCCGCUCGCACAUGCCCGAGCCGCAGCCCCGCGAGCAGGCAGCGCCGGCCCCCCGCCCCGCGGCCCCGGGCCCCGGCUCCGGCGCCGUCCCUCCUCCCCGGCCGGGCGCCGCGGCCCCGGCAUGAGGAGCGGGCGAUGAUCCCCGCCAACGCCUCCGCCAGGAAGGGGCCCGAGGGCAAGUAUCCGCUGCACUACCUCGUGUGGCACAACCGCCACCGCGAGCUGGAGAAGGAGGUCCGCGCGGGCCAGGUGGACAUCGAGCAGCUGGAUCCCCGCGGCCGGACUCCCCUGCACCUGGCCACCACGCUGGGGCACCUUGAGUGUGCCCGUGUGCUCCUGGCGCACGGCGCAGACGUGGGCAGGGAGAAUCGCAGCGGCUGGACAGUGCUCCAGGAGGCUGUGAGUACCCGGGACCUGGAGCUGGUGCAGCUGGUGCUUCGGUACCGGGACUACCAGCGGGUGGUGAAGCGGCUGGCGGGCAUCCCCGUGCUCCUGGAGAAGCUGCGCAAGGCCCAGGACUUCUACGUGGAGAUGAAAUGGGAGUUCACUAGCUGGGUGCCCCUGGUGUCCAAGAUCUGCCCUAGUGACACCUACAAAGUGUGGAAGAGCGGCCAGAACCUGAGGGUAGACACCACACUCCUGGGCUUUGACCACAUGACCUGGCAGCGAGGGAACCGCAGCUUUGUCUUCAGGGGCCAAGACACAAGCGCCGUGGUCAUGGAGAUUGACCACGACCGCCGGGUGGUGUACACAGAGACUCUGGCACUGGCUGGGCAGGACCGGGAGCUGCUGCUGGCUGCUGCUCAGCCCACUGAGGAACAGGUGCUGAGCCGGCUUACCGCGCCCGUCGUCACCACUCAGCUUGACACCAAGAAUAUCUCCUUUGAGAGGAACAAGACUGGCAUCCUGGGCUGGCGCAGUGAAAAGACGGAGAUGGUGAAUGGGUAUGAAGCUAAGGUGAGGCUGCAGCUCCCAGCUGCCAGCCCAGCUGCACUCUUGCCUACAGCAAGCUGUACAGGGGAUUCUGACCUCCCUUCCCCAGCCCUGGAGGUGUAUGGGGCAUCUAACGUGGAGCUCAUCACCCGCACACGGACAGAACAUCUUUCAGAACAGCACAAGGGCAAGGUCAAAGGCUGUAAGACACCUUUGCAGUCCUUCCUGGGAAUCGCUGAGCAGCACGGGGGCCCCCAAAAUGGGACCCUGAUCACUCAGACUCUGAGCCAAGCCAACCCCACUGCCAUCACUGCAGAAGAAUACUUCAACCCCAACUUUGAGCUGGGCAACCGUGAUAUGGGCCGCCCCAUGGAACUGACCACCAAGACACAGAAGUUCAAGGCCAAGCUGUGGCUGUGUGAGGAGCAUCCCCUGUCCCUGUGUGAGCAGGUGGCCCCCAUCAUUGACCUCAUGGCCGUCAGCAAUGCGCUUUUUGCCAAGCUCCGGGACUUCAUCACCCUGCGUCUGCCUCCUGGCUUCCCAGUUAAGAUUGAAAUCCCGAUCUUCCACAUCCUCAACGCCCGCAUCACCUUCGGGAACCUCAACGGCUGCGACGAACCGGUGCCAUCGGUGCGAGGCAGCCCCAGCAGCGAGACGCCUUCCCCAGGCAGCGACUCCUCCAGCGUCAGCAGCUCCAGCUCCACGACCUCCUGCCGCGGCUGCGAGAUCUCCCCAGCGUUGUUCGAGGCCCCGCGCGGCUACAGCAUGAUGGGCGGCCAGCGGGAGGCGGCGACCCGGGACGACGACGACGACCUGCUGCAAUUCGCCAUCCAGCAGAGCCUGCUUGAGGCGGGCAGUGAGUAUGACCAGGUCACCAUCUGGGAGGCGCUAACCAACAGCAAGCCAGGCACCCACCCCAUGUCCUACGAGGGUCGCCGACAGGACAGGUCAGUGCCCGCUGGGCCGGAGAGAAUCCUCCGGAGAGGAUCCUGUCUCCCCUAAGCCAGGACACAGCCGGAGAACCCGCGGGGCCCUCGGCAGGGACCCUCCUGGUAUCGGGAUGGCUUCUGCCACCACUCCUGCCUCCGAGGCGGCAGGCAGGGGUCAGGGAUCCAGGCUUCACCGCGGAGUUCAGACUCUCCCCAGGCAUUGACGGGGAGAACUUGGUAGGGUCUGGGCUCCGCCACGACCAGGUGGGGGCCAGGACGCCGCGGGACUGACCGCCUCCACUAGAGGGUGGUGGCCGCGGGCCGCCCUGGAGCCUCCACGCCGUGUCCCGGCCCCGGCCGGUGGGUGGGUGCGCCCGGGAGCCCGCGACAUUCCUUCCCCACCCCCAGGAGCGCCCCGCCCACGCCGCAGCGCCAGCCUGCGCCCCCGGCGUCAGUGCCCAGCCCUCGGCCCAGCUCAGGGCCAGGUUCCGGCGGCCACGUGUUCCGGAGCUACGACGAGCAGCUGCGGCUGGCGAUGGAACUGUCGGCGCAGGAGCAGGAGGAGAGGCGGCGGCGCGCGCGCCAGGAGGAGGAGGAGCUGGAGCGCAUCCUGAGGCUCUCACUGACCGAGCAGUAGCGCCCCCUGCCGGGACCCUCGCCAGCGCCACGCGCGCCACGCCCAGGGCCAGGAGCCAGACAAACCCCGGCCUGCGCGCCUGCAGAGCGGCGGCUGGAGACUGGAGCCACCGCCUCGCGGGUGCAGCAGCACAGCAGGCACGGUUCGGGGAGGGAUUCGGCAUGGCCGCGGGGUACCUUCCCAGGCCAGGGCCCUGGAGGCAACUGGCACGGCCUGGUCCCCCUGCUUUGCUGUAUUCUGAUUCCCCAACCCGCUCCCCUGGGCUCAGAUCUGUCCUGUCCUAGGGCGGAGCCAGGCGGUCCUGAGGGGGAGAUGAAUCCUUAGAGGAGCGCUGUCCCUAUCCCUUGCUCCUUCUGGCCGGUCCGCAUUUCUGUUCACUAACCCCACUCCAGGACACUGCCCCUGAAGCCUUUGCAUCUCUGCUCUUCACUCCUGGGGGGCAGCUGAGCUCCCCGCGUGCUGUGUCACUGCUUUGUUCCAGACACAAACCAGCACGUCUAGGGCCCAGCCCCUCCCCCACCCCGGCAUUUCAGCGUCAAGUGCACUUAGCGGGGUACCCGGCUCCCCCAGCCCCCACACCCGUCCUGGGUCUCAGGGUGGUUCCAGCUUCUCCUUGGGCAGCCAGAAGUUGGAGUCCCAUCCCCCAAGGCACAUUUUUUUUUUUUUUUUUUUGUGAUCAGGGAGUGUGUCCAACGUAGCCCCCUGGCCUGUGCAAGCCCUGACUCCCUCAUGGUGCCUCGGAGAGUGGGGAGCAUAUUGGGCUGGGGUAAGCACUAGACCCAAGUAGACUGGACACAAAGGGCUCGCCCAGGGCCCUGGCGCCACCCCCACCCCUUCCCACCAGCUGCUGCUAGCCUCUGUGGUUGUACAUCCCACUUGCCCCCACACGGAGACUGACUCUAAAACCCUUCAUCCAAUGGUGCUAACCCCCGGCUCUCCCCUGCCCCACCUCACCCACCCAGAGAAGCACAGACCCCGCCAGGGGCAGGGGCCCACCGCACACCCUUGUCCCGGGCCUGUCUGGGACUGGCCUUCCCGGCUCAGCCAGUGAGGCUCAGAAGGGACACAAAGAGGGAUGGAAGAAAAGAACAAAGAGAAACUGUUCCUCCCACCCCCUUCCCUGAUGCCAGGGGCACCAGACUGAUUCUGAGGCACAAAUAAAAGAGGCUUCAUACCGGA